ACUCGCUCGUCCCCGGCUUCCGAGCACAGCAUGGCGGUCAAGGUGCAGACAACUAAGCGAGGGGAUCCUCAUGAGUUAAGAAACAUAUUUCUACAGUAUGCCAGUACUGAGGUUGAUGGAGAGCGUUAUAUGACCCCAGAAGACUUUGUUCAGCGCUAUCUUGGACUGUAUAAUGAUCCAAAUAGUAACCCAAAGAUCGUGCAGCUCUUGGCAGGAGUAGCUGAUCAAACCAAGGAUGGGUUGAUCUCCUAUCAAGAGUUUUUGGCAUUUGAAUCUGUUUUAUGUGCUCCAGAUUCCAUGUUCAUAGUGGCUUUCCAGUUGUUUGACAAGAGUGGAAAUGGAGAGGUGACAUUUGAAAAUGUCAAAGAAAUUUUUGGACAGACUAUUAUUCAUCAUCAUAUCCCUUUUAACUGGGAUUGUGAAUUUAUCCGACUGCAUUUUGGGCAUAACCGGAAGAAGCAUCUUAACUACACAGAAUUCACGCAGUUUCUCCAGGAGCUGCAAUUGGAACAUGCAAGACAAGCCUUUGCACUCAAAGACAAAAGCAAAAGUGGCAUGAUUUCUGGUCUGGAUUUCAGUGACAUCAUGGUUACCAUUAGAUCUCACAUGCUUACUCCUUUUGUGGAGGAGAACUUAGUUUCAGCAGCUGGAGGAAGUAUCUCACACCAGGUUAGCUUCUCCUACUUCAAUGCAUUUAACUCGUUACUGAAUAACAUGGAGCUUGUUCGUAAGAUAUAUAGCACUCUAGCUGGCACAAGGAAAGAUGUUGAAGUCACAAAGGAGGAAUUUGCCCAGAGUGCCAUACGCUAUGGACAAGUCACACCACUAGAAAUUGAUAUUCUAUAUCAGCUUGCAGACUUAUAUAAUGCUUCAGGGCGCUUGACUUUGGCAGAUAUUGAGAGAAUAGCCCCAUUGGCUGAGGGGGCCUUACCUUACAACCUGGCAGAACUUCAGAGACAGCAGUCUCCUGGGUUAGGCAGGCCUAUCUGGCUCCAGAUUGCCGAGUCUGCUUACAGAUUCACUCUGGGCUCAGUUGCUGGAGCUGUGGGAGCCACUGCAGUGUAUCCUAUAGAUCUGGUGAAGACCCGAAUGCAAAACCAGCGUGGCUCUGGCUCUGUUGUUGGGGAGCUAAUGUACAAAAACAGCUUUGACUGUUUUAAGAAAGUCUUGCGUUAUGAGGGCUUCUUUGGACUCUACAGGGGUCUGAUACCACAACUUAUAGGGGUUGCUCCAGAAAAGGCCAUUAAACUGACUGUUAAUGAUUUUGUUCGGGACAAAUUUACCAGAAGAGAUGGCUCUGUUCCACUUCCAGCAGAAGUUCUUGCUGGAGGCUGUGCUGGAGGCUCUCAGGUCAUUUUUACCAACCCAUUGGAGAUAGUGAAGAUUCGUCUGCAAGUAGCUGGAGAGAUCACCACGGGACCCAGAGUCAGCGCCCUGAAUGUGCUCCGGGACUUGGGAAUUUUUGGUCUGUAUAAGGGUGCCAAAGCGUGUUUCCUCCGAGACAUUCCCUUCUCUGCAAUCUAUUUUCCUGUUUAUGCUCAUUGCAAACUACUUCUGGCUGAUGAAAAUGGACACGUGGGAGGUUUAAAUCUUCUUGCAGCUGGAGCCAUGGCAGGUGUCCCAGCUGCAUCUCUGGUGACCCCUGCUGAUGUCAUCAAGACAAGACUGCAGGUGGCUGCCCGCGCUGGCCAGACGACAUACAGUGGUGUCAUCGACUGUUUCAGGAAGAUUCUCCGGGAAGAAGGGCCCUCAGCAUUUUGGAAAGGGACUGCAGCUCGAGUGUUUCGAUCCUCUCCCCAGUUUGGUGUUACCUUGGUCACUUAUGAACUUCUCCAGCGGUGGUUUUACAUUGAUUUUGGAGGCCUCAAACCCGCUGGUUCAGAACCAACACCUAAGUCACGCAUUGCAGACCUUCCUCCUGCCAACCCUGAUCACAUCGGUGGAUACAGACUCGCCACAGCCACGUUUGCAGGCAUCGAAAACAAAUUUGGCCUUUAUCUCCCGAAAUUUAAGUCUCCUAGUGUUGCUGUGGUUCAGCCAAAGGCAGCAGUGGCAGCCACUCAGUGAUGAGACAACUGUUGAGUGUGGCAAAAUGGCGCCUUGAAGAAAGAGGCCUAGGAGAGCAGCCCUGUAAUGUAUCCAGUCAGCUGCAUGGUACUGACUGAGCUGAGGAGUCAAACUCUUCUUUCUGUAUGACAUAUACAUAUACUUGUUUAUAAAAUAAUCAUUUGCCCAGGGAAAAAACCACAACGCUGUUUCAAGCUUUAGUCUUAUGUGUUGAAAUGUUUUUGUAAGCCUUGGCAUGAAUUAGUGUUCUAGACUCUGCUUUGCACAGCUUGCACUUACAGUGAUUGUACAUAUUGUACAUCUUUGUACAGAGACAUCUUGGCACCUCAUCCCAACAAAUCACAUUUGUAGAAAUGUAAUGCGGUUCUGAGUGGCUUGAAAUGUACAGAAUGUUUUGAAAGUGUUUUAUUAAGAAUCACACAAAAAUAAAUGUAUUAAAAUUAAAUUCAUUCUCUUAUUGGUGACUUAUGGAAAUAAAGCAUCAAUAUUGGAUGUAUUUAAUUCCUAGUUUGUUUUCCAUUCUGGAAUAAAAAGGUAUUUGCUGAUAAAAGGCAUAACGAGACAUAGUGCUGCUACCACUGAAUAAGUGAUACUUUGGAAAGAUGCAUGCCAGUGGAUGCCAGAGGACCAGGCUAAUGACUUGUGUGUGCUGAUGUGUUUCCAUUUGUAUUUAAUGUGUGUAGACCCUCCUCUGUUCAUCAAUCAAAAAGCAUUUCCUAGGCAGCUCCUCGCCUGUCAGUGUGCAUAUGGAAACAGGGACAUCUCCAUCAUUACUGGCUUAGUUUUGCUUUCCUUUGACACAGUAAGGCAAAGGCCAAGCUUUCAAAAGAGUAAAGGAUACUUUCACAAUUUCCCUUCAUAUGGAUAUGAUUCCAGUCAAAAAUAAAAUGCACACCAAAAUGUAUACAUGUAGUUGGAUUUUUCUUUGUAAAUAUACUGAUAAUACUUUUUGUUCUGAUUGACUACUGAUUGCAAAUAACUCAUGAUCGGGUUCGCCCUUUCUUCCACCUUUAUAGAAAACAGAAAAAUUAGUUUUAGAAAGGGCUAGCGCAGAGUGAAGGGAGGGAAGAAGAAAGAGAAGAAAAGCUCUAUAUGGUGAUUUAGUGGGGUCUAGGUUCUUACUUUGGAAUCCAAAUGCAAACUGUUCUAAAAGUCACUCAUCAAGGGCGUGAUUACUAAUUUGGAUCUAAACAUAGAUCUUGACAGCCACAUCUACACUUUGAUAUGGAUGUGAUUUGAUGUGCAGUAUCAGAAUUUAUUUACCUUACCAAAGUGCUCUGGGAAGACAUUAUUGCUACUGCCAGUAAGCUGGGAUAUGAGAAUGUAUGCAAAUAUUUUCAAGAGGCGAGCCUGGAGACAGACCAAGUUACUUAGUAUCCUGCACAGUGCUCCUCGAUUGAUGGCUGACAGCCCUGUGACUGCAACUGUAGGCUCCCUGGAGGCCCUCCAGGAACAAAAGAAUUAGCUUUGAAAGCAAGUUAUUUUCAAAUGUAUUAGAUUGGUCUCAUGGGAGUGGAACAAAUAAUAAUACAGUUGUUUUGCUACUACCACUUGUUAGAAAUAUAUAAGUAGUCCAUGGAUAUGUGAUUACAAAAGAAUCCUAUGUAUGUAUCUAGAGUGAGAUGGGAAAGUGUCCCGCUUACCCUCCUUCUACCUCCACCACUUCCUGGCCCAGAGGUAAUCACUGCUAACAGGUUACAGCAUGAAUAUGUAGUCUGUUUUUCAUAACUCUAUAGAAAUAUAUGUACAUAUUUAUAUUUUAGAAACAGGAUUAUGUUAUGUGUGUGUUAUUCUGUGUCUUGCUUUUGUUCACUUAAUGUGUUUUGGAUAUCUUUCCAUGUCAGUUUAUAAAGUUUUAUUUUUAAUGGC